UUUGCAGAUCUGAAGAGCACAGUCAAGACCACAGACACCCGUGGAGGCUCCCCCAAGACAUCUGCUUCUCUGGGACUGGGGACCUCGCUCAGGACCGUGGGGAGUUGGCUGAAGGACUUGGGGAGCCCAGAAGCUGCCACCGAACCAAGAACCACCUCUGUGCAGAAAAGCAACCACCUUGUUCUCUAUUCUGCUGCCCGAGACAACCACAUCCUCCUCCUCCUACACCCAAAGGCUCCCAUGGAGAGCUCAGAUGUGGAGCUGGACCUCCAGAGGAGCGUGCAGGCUGUGCUCCGGGAGCUCAGCACCCAGGCCCCUGCCCUGCAGAGCAACCAAGGCAUGUGGAGGUGGUCCCUGCACAAGAAGGUCGAGCGAGAUCCCGGUAAGAGCCCAGUGCUGGUCCGCAUUCUUCUCAGAGAACUGGAGAAGGUGAGUUCCUGGACCUCAGGGAGGAAGACGGGGAUGAAAGGAAGAGAGGGGCCAAUUGGGCAGGGGCUCAGUCCUGGCAGCGCUAUAUCUCAUAAGCUUUGGUUGCCUGCAUGAUUUUUACCAUAUGCAUCUCCCUCCUGUACUUUUACGUAAGCAGUAUUUUCUUUACGUCGACUCUCAUUGUUUUACUUGAAUAAACAUCUUUCAAAAAGAAGCACUAUAACGCGACCACAAAUGGAAAACCCGCAUCACUUGUCAGAAACAGAAGGCGGAAAGCCAGGACCUCCGGCAUGUCAUCAUUCCCUUGCUGCACACUGUAAUGUACGUGCUCACCAAGGCCACAGGAAUCACAGAAGAGCUCUACCAGAGAAUCUAUGCCUUUUGCACAAGGUUACUGACCCUGCCCACCCCCUACUGCACAGUCGCCUUGGACUGCGCGAUAAGGCUGAAAACGGAGAUGGCUGUCCCAGGAUACCGGGGAGCUCAAAAGCCUCCACACCUUCUGUAGGAAGGUGGAGAAUGGGAGUCAGAGACUUGGGGGCUGUUUGGCCAAAGUGGUCUGGUUUGCAGGGACACUGUACCAAAGGAUGGUCAUUGCCGAACAGAACUUGACGAAUGAGCUGUAUCCCUACCAGGAGAGAGUGUUCCUCUUCGUGGAUCCUGAGCUGGUGUCUGCGUCUGUGUGCAGUGCUCUGCUACUGGAGAUCGAGGCGGCCCAGGCGCAGCAGACACCAGAGACCUGCAUGCGCCACGUGGUCUCCCACGCCCUGCAGGCGGCUCUGGGGGAGGCCUGUCACGCAGGCGCUCUGCACAGGAAGCUGCAGGCCAGCCCUCGCCGCACCCUGGAGCACUAUUUCCACGCCGUGGUGGCCGCCUUGGAGCAGAUGGCCAGCGAGGCCAGCCCGAGCCGGGAGGGACACGUAGAGAGGCUGGAGGAGAUUUACUGCUCGCUGCUGGGUCCCGCGGCGGGGCGCUGCGGUGGUGACCUUGUCCAAGAGCGGCCACCAAGCAUUCCCCUGCCCAGCCCCUACAUCACCUUCCACUUGUGGACCGGUGAGGAGCAGCUCUGGAAGGAACUGGUGCUCUUCCUCCGCCCAAGAUCCCAGCUGCGCCUCAGUGCUGACUUGGAGGUCUUGGAUCUGCAGGGCCUCCGGCCGGACCGGGAGUUGGCCCGGGUUUCUGUGCUGUCCACUGACAGCGGCAUUGAGCGGGACCUUCCCACGGGGGCUGAUGAGCUGCCUGCACCCGGCAGCCCUGAGAUGGAGCGAGCCGGGCUGCAGCGCAAAGGGGGCAUCAAGAAGCGUGCAUGGCCCCUGGACUUCUUGAUGCCUGGCAGCUGGGACGGGCCCCCAGGGCUGCACCGGAGGACAGGCCGGCCCAGUGGGGAUGGGGAAAUGCUGCCCGGCGUGUCCCGGCUGCACACAGCCCGGGUACUUGUGCUCGGAGAUGACAGGAUGCUGGGGCGCCUGGCCCAGGCCUACCACAGACUCAGGAAACGGGAGACCCAGAAGUUCUGCCUCACUCCCAGACUCAGCCUGCAGCUCUACUACAUCCCCGUGCUGGCGCCUGAGAAGCCUGCAGCAUCCAGGCAGCCGGAGCUGGGAGAGCUGGCUACGUUCCUGGGCCGCGUAGACCCGUGGUACCAGAGCAACGUCAACACGCUGUGCCCCGCCAUCCACAAGCUGGCUGAGAUGCCUCCUUCCCUGGACACAUCCCGGACUGUGGACCCCUUCAUCCUAGACGUCAUCACCUACUACAUCCGCAUGGGCACCCAACCCAUCUAUUUCCAGAUCUACACAGUCAAGAUCUUUUUCAGUGACCUGAGCCAAGACCCUACUGAGGACAUUUUCCUCAUUGAACUGAAGGUGAAGAUCCAAGAUUCUAAAUUCCCCAAAGAUGGCUUUUCACCCAGGAGGAGAGGCGUGGCUGAGGGCCCAGGGGCAGAGCUCUCCCUAUGCUACCAGAAGGCCUUGCUUAGCCACCGGCCCCGAGAGGUCACCGUUUCCCUGCGGGCCACUGGGCUGAUCCUGAAGGCCAUUCCAGCCAGCGACACAGAAGUUUCAGGGUCUAGCCAUUGCCCCCUGCCUGCUGCUCCUGUCACAGACCACACAUGUCUGAAUGUCAACGUGACAGAGGUUGUCAAGUCCUCCAACUUGGCGGGAAAGUCCUUCUCUACAGUGACCAACACCUUCAGGACGAACAAUAUCCAGAUCCAGAGCCGGGACCAGAGGCUGCUGACACUGUCGCUGGACAAGGACGAUCAACGCACUUUCAGGGAUGUGGUCAGAUUCGAGGUUGCUCCCUGCCCAGAACCAUGUUCUGGGGCCCAGAAGUCCAAGGCACCGUGGCUCAAUUUGCAUGGGCAACAGGAGGUGGAAGCAAUCAAAGCCAAGCCCAAGCCCCUUCUGAUGCCCAUCAACACAUUCUCUGGUAUUGUCCAGUGAGCCUGCAGGGACAGCAGGCCCAGGAGGAAGGAUACACUACCCCACCAACUCCAAACACUCACACCAACAGCCAGAGCAAGGCCCGGCUCCACACGGCAGCUUUGGCCUUGACCAGGAGCCAGCGAGUGCCUGGGAGCACAGGGAGCCUACCCUGGGGACUGUGAUGAGGAAGGGCCCACAUGGAGGUCUACGGAUGGCCCAGGCAAUGCUGUCGCUGCUUGAGAACAUACACACCAAGCCCAGCUUCUCAUACAAAUGUCUACUCCUUCAUUUAGCUUCAAUUCCCACUUCUCCCACUGUCCUCUCCCACCCAAGCUCCCCAUCCAGCCCUUAAAACCAGGGUUAAAGCUGCUGUCUUGGCCAGAGCCCUGUGGCCUAGGGGAAAAUUGGAAGCAAGGAACAGCAACAGCACCACCUCCCUCCCAAGUCUCUUCCCUUCCCACUCUCAGGCCACUGCCCACCUCACUCAGCCCAGGCAGGUGUCUCUAUCAGGUGAGAGAAAAAUGUCAGACUCAAUAAAUGUACACUGAAGUCUUUCUGCUUUCAUCUC